CUGCGCCCGGCCAAGAUUGUCUUUUAAAACACCCCUCUGGAAUGGAUGAACCUGGAGGACAUUAUGCUAAGUGAAAUAAGCCAGACACAGAAAGACAAAUAGUGCAUGACCUCACUUAUCUGUGGAAUCUAAAAAAGAAUUGAACUCGUAGAAGCAGAGUAGAGCAGUGGUUAUGGUGGUGAGGGCACAGGGGAAGGCGGGGGAUGUAGGUCAAAGGGUACAAGCUUUCAGCUUUCAGAUAAACACGUUUUAACCAGGCAGAAUGGCUUGUGCCUGUAAUCCCAGCACUUUGGGAGGCCAAGGCGGGAGCAUCGCUUGACGCCAGGAGUGCAAGGCCAGCCUGAACAACAUAGCAAGACCCUGUCUCCACAAAAAAAUUUAAAAUCAGCCAAGCAUGGUGGCACACACCUGUAAUUCCAGCUACACGGAAGGCUGAGGUGGGAGGAUCUCUUGAGCCCAGGAGUUCGAGGCUACAGUGAGCUUUGAUGGUGCCACUGCACUCCAGCCUGGGCAACAGAGCAAGACCUCAUCUCUAAAAGAAAAAAGUUCCAGAGACCUAAGGUACAGCAUGGUGACUAUAAUUAAUAAUAGCAGGCCAGGUGUGGCGGCUCAUACCUAUAAUCGCAGCACUUUGGGAGGCCGAGGCAGGCAGAUUGCUUGAGCUCAAGAGUUUGAGACCAGCCUGGGCAACAUGAGACUCCAUCUCUACUAAAAAUACAAAAAUUAACCAGGCACGGUGGUGCCCACCCGUAGCCCCGGCCACUUAGGAGGCUGAGGCACGAGAAUUGCUUGAACUGGGAGGGAGAAGUUGCAGUGAGCCAAGAUUGCGCCACUGCACUCCAGCAUGGGUGACAGAGCGAGACUCCGUCUCAAAAUAAUAAUAAUUAUUAUAGCAUACUGUUUUCUUGAAACUUGCUGAGGAAUUAGACUCAAGUGUUCUCACCACACACACCAGAAAGGUGUCUAGGUGAGGUGUUGGAUGUGUUGUUAGCUUGGUUGUGGUAAUCACUUCACAACACAUAAUGGAUAUCAAAAUAUCAUGUAACCUUAAAUAGAUGUAAUUUCUAUUUGUCAAUGAUGCCUCAGCAAAGCUAGGGAGAAAAUAAAAAGGAUCCUUCUGUGCAACAGCCCGCAUGUCCAUUACCGAUGACUGGAUAAAGAAAACGUGCUCCACCCAUGCAGUGGAAUACUACGCAGCCAUAAAACGGAAUGAAGCUCGGAUCCAGGCUAGAACGUAGGCUGGUGGUCCAGGCCGUGGUGCCUGCCAGGUGAUGUGGGGCAAAGCCCCCCGCACAGGCCACUGAGAGCUCCGGACACGCACCCGGCUGCCACCAUGGCCCGCCUAGCCGCAGUGCUCUGGAAUCUGUGUGUCACCGCCGUCCUGGUCACCUCGGCCACCCAAGGCCUGAGCCGGGCCGGGCUCCCGUUCGGGCUGAUGCGCCGGGAGCUGGCGUGUGAAGGCUACCCCAUCGAGCUGCGGUGCCCCGGCAGCGACGUCAUCAUGGUGGAGAAUGCCAACUACGGGCGCACGGACGACAAGAUUUGCGAUGCUGACCCUUUCCAGAUGGAGAAUGUGCAGUGCUACCUGCCGGACGCCUUCAAGAUCAUGUCACAGAGGUGUAACAACCGCACCCAGUGCGUGGUGGUCGCCGGCUCGGAUGCCUUUCCUGACCCCUGUCCUGGGACCUACAAGUACCUGGAGGUGCAGUACGACUGUGUCCCCUACAUAGAAGUGGAGCAGAAAGUCUUCGUGUGCCCAGGGACCCUGCAGAAGGUGCUGGAGCCCACCUCGACACACGAGUCAGAGCACCAGUCUGGCGCAUGGUGCAAGGACCCGCUGCAGGCGGGUGACCGCAUCUACGUGAUGCCCUGGAUCCCCUACCGCACGGACACACUGACUGAGUAUGCCUCGUGGGAGGACUACGUGGCCGCCCGCCACACCACCACCUACCGCCUGCCCAACCGCGUGGAUGGCACAGGCUUUGUGGUCUACGAUGGUGCCGUCUUCUACAACAAGGAGCGCACGCGCAACAUCGUCAAGUAUGACCUACGGACGCGCAUCAAGAGCGGGGAGACGGUCAUCAAUACCGCCAACUACCAUGACACCUCGCCCUACCGCUGGGGCGGAAAGACCGACAUUGACCUGGCGGUGGACGAGAACGGGCUGUGGGUCAUCUACGCCACUGAGGGCAACAACGGGCGGCUGGUGGUGAGCCAGCUGAACCCCUACACACUGCGCUUUGAGGGCACGUGGGAGACGGGUUACGACAAGCGCUCGGCAUCCAACGCCUUCAUGGUGUGUGGGGUCCUGUACGUCCUGCGUUCCGUGUACGUGGAUGAUGACAGCGAGGCGGCUGGCAACCGCGUGGACUAUGCCUUCAACACCAAUGCCAACCGCGAGGAGCCUGUCAGCCUCACCUUCCCCAACCCCUACCAGUUCAUCUCCUCCGUUGACUACAACCCUCGCGACAACCAGCUGUACGUCUGGAACAACUAUUUCGUGGUGCGCUACAGCCUGGAGUUCGGGCCGCCCGACCCCAGUGCUGGUGAGGACGACUCACUUCCAGGCCCAGCCACUUCCCCACCCCUCAGCACGACCACCACAGCCAGGCCCACGCCCCUCACCAGCACAGCCUCGCCCGCAGCCACCACCCCGCUCCGCCGGGCACCCCUCACCACGCACCCAGUGGGUGCCAUCAACCAGCUGGGACCUGAUCUGCCUCCAGCCACAGCCCCAGUCCCCAGCACCCGGCGGCCCCCAGCCCCGAAUCUACACGUGUCCCCUGAGCUCUUCUGCGAGCCCCGAGAGGUACGGCGGGUCCAGUGGCCGGCCACCCAGCAGGGCAUGCUGGUGGAGAGGCCCUGCCCCAAGGGGACUCGAGGAAUUGCCUCCUUCCAGUGUCUACCAGCCUUGGGGCUCUGGAACCCCCGGGGCCCUGACCUCAGCAACUGCACCUCCCCCUGGGUCAACCAGGUGGCCCAGAAGAUCAAGAGUGGGGAGAACGCGGCCAACAUCGCCAGCGAGCUGGCCCGACACACCCGGGGCUCCAUCUACGCGGGGGACGUCUCCUCCUCUGUGAAGCUGAUGGAGCAGCUGCUGGACAUCCUGGAUGCCCAGCUGCAGGCCCUGCGGCCCAUCGAGCGCGAGUCAGCCGGCAAGAACUACAACAAGAUGCACAAGCGAGAGAGAACUUGUAAGGAUUAUAUCAAGGCCGUGGUGGAGACAGUGGACAAUCUGCUCCGGCCAGAAGCUCUGGAGUCCUGGAAGGACAUGAAUGCCACGGAGCAGGUGCACACGGCCACCAUGCUCCUCGACGUCCUGGAGGAGGGCGCCUUCCUGCUGGCCGACAAUGUCAGGGAGCCUGCCCGCUUCCUGGCUGCCAAGGAGAACGUGGUCCUGGAGGUCACAGUCCUGAACACAGAGGGCCAGGUGCAGGAGCUGGUGUUCCCCCAGGAGGAGUACCCGAGAAAGAACUCCAUCCAGCUGUCUGCCAAAACCAUCAAGCAGAACAGCCGCAAUGGGGUGGUCAAAGUUGUCUUCAUCCUCUACAACAACCUGGGCCUCUUCCUGUCCACGGAGAAUGCCACAGUGAAGCUGGCCGGCGAAGCAGGCCCGGGUGGCCCUGGGGGCGCCUCUCUAGUGGUGAACUCACAGGUCAUCGCAGCAUCCAUCAACAAGGAGUCCAGCCGCGUCUUCCUCAUGGACCCUGUCAUCUUCACCGUGGCCCACCUGGAGGACAAGAACCACUUCAAUGCUAACUGCUCCUUCUGGAACUACUCGGAGCGUUCCAUGCUGGGCUACUGGUCGACCCAAGGCUGCCGCCUGGUGGAGUCCAACAAGACCCAUACCACGUGUGCCUGCAGCCACCUCACCAACUUCGCUGUGCUCAUGGCUCACCGUGAGAUCUACCAGGGCCGCAUCAACGAGCUGCUGCUGUCGGUCAUCACCUGGGUGGGCAUUGUGAUCUCCCUGGUCUGCUUGGCCAUCUGCAUCUCCACCUUCUGCUUCCUGCGGGGGCUGCAGACCGACCGCAACACCAUCCACAAGAACCUGUGCAUCAACCUCUUCCUGGCUGAGCUGCUCUUCCUGGUCGGGAUCGACAAGACUCAGUAUGAGAUUGCCUGCCCCAUCUUCGCCGGCCUGCUGCACUAUUUCUUCCUGGCUGCCUUCUCCUGGCUGUGCCUGGAGGGCGUGCACCUCUACCUGCUACUAGUGGAGGUGUUUGAGAGCGAGUAUUCCCGCACCAAGUACUACUACCUGGGUGGCUACUGCUUCCCGGCCCUGGUGGUGGGCAUCGCGGCUGCCAUUGACUACCGCAGCUACGGCACCGAGAAGGCCUGCUGGCUCCGAGUGGACAAUUACUUCAUCUGGAGUUUCAUCGGGCCAGUCUCCUUCGUUAUCGUGGUCAACCUGGUGUUCCUCAUGGUGACCCUGCACAAGAUGAUCCGAAGCUCAUCUGUGCUCAAGCCCGACUCCAGCCGCCUGGACAACAUUAAAUCCUGGGCGCUGGGGGCCAUCGCGCUGCUGUUCCUGCUGGGCCUCACCUGGGCUUUCGGCCUCCUCUUCAUCAACAAGGAGUCGGUGGUCAUGGCCUAUCUCUUCACCACCUUCAACGCCUUCCAGGGGGUCUUCAUCUUCGUCUUUCACUGCGCCUUACAGAAGAAGGUGCACAAGGAGUACAGCAAGUGCCUGCGUCACUCCUACUGCUGCAUCCGCUCCCCACCCGGGGGCACUCACGGAUCCCUCAAGACCUCAGCCAUGCGAAGCAACACCCGCUACUACACAGGGACCCAGAGCCGAAUUCGGAGGAUGUGGAAUGACACUGUGAGGAAACAGACGGAGUCCUCCUUCAUGGCGGGUGACAUCAACAGCACCCCCACCCUGAACCGAGGUACCAUGGGGAACCACCUGCUGACCAACCCCGUGCUGCAGCCCCGUGGGGGCACCAGUCCCUACAACACCCUCAUCGCCGAGUCAGUGGGCUUCAAUCCCUCCUCGCCCCCUGUCUUCAACUCCCCAGAACUGGAGCCUGGACUUGCAUUUCGAGCUCAUCCUUGCCUUUUCUCUUCUCUCUUCUGGCUGCCACCUGCAGGGAGCUACCGGGAACCCAAGCACCCCUUGGGAGGCCGGGAAGCCUGUGGCAUGGACACCCUGCCCCUGAACGGCAACUUCAAUAACAGUUACUCCUUGCGAAGUGGGGAUUUCCCUCCCGGGGAUGGGGGCCCUGAGCCGCCCCGAGGCCGGAACCUAGCCGAUGCGGCGGCCUUUGAGAAGAUGAUCAUCUCAGAGCUGGUGCACAACAACCUGCGGGGGAGCAGCAGCGCGGCCAAGGGCCCUCCACCGCCUGAGCCCCCUGUGCCACCUGUGCCAGGGGGCGGGGGCGAGGAAGAGGCGGGCGGGCCCGGGGGUGCUGACCGGGCCGAGAUUGAACUUCUCUAUAAGGCCCUGGAGGAGCCUCUGCUGCUGCCCCGGGCCCAGUCGGUGCUGUACCAGAGCGAUCUGGACGAGUCGGAGAGCUGCACGGCCGAGGACGGCGCCACCAGCCGGCCCCUCUCCUCCCCUCCUGGCCGGGACUCCCUCUAUGCCAGCGGGGCCAACCUGCGGGACUCACCCUCCUACCCGGACAGCAGCCCUGAGGGGCCCAGUGAGGCCCUGCCCCCACCCCCUCCCGCACCCCCCGGCCCCCCCGAAAUCUACUACACCUCGCGCCCGCCAGCCCUGGUGGCCCGGAAUCCCCUGCAGGGCUACUACCAGGUGCGGCGUCCUAGCCACGAGGGCUACCUGGCAGCCCCAGGCCUUGAGGGGCCAGGGCCCGAUGGGGACGGGCAGAUGCAGCUGGUCACCAGUCUCUGAGGGCACCUCAUGGACCAGGGGCUGGUGGCCCAGGCCAGGGAGGGAACCCUGGGCAGGGCUCUGGUGGGAGAGGGAGACAGAUGGAGGCAGUGGCUGGUGGGCCACUCUCUCCAGGUGCCCCUCAGCCAUGGGCCCUACAGUCCCCUCAGGGGACUCUAACCUGGGGGCCUGAGGUGCCAGGGUUCACAGACAGGGUUUCCCACCAGCCACACGCACCAGCUCUAUUUGGGGGAAGUGUAGUGAGGAGGAGCCCAGAGGACCCCAGGGGAGUGAGGAGGGAGAACUUGGAAGGGUGCAGCCCACUUCCAGACUCUCCCCUCUCCCACCCUUCUACCCUGUGAAGGGAAAUGAGGGCUUUAGUUUCCUGGGCAGGGAGGGGCAGCUUCUGAGGUUGCCAAAGGCCCCCACUGGAUGGAACCUGUUAGCUGCUCCUCUCCGCAGCCAGAAAUGCUGCCGGCUGCACCCAGAGGGAGCAGUGAGGCAGGACAGAUGGACAGGUUCCUCCUGCGCUGUAAUUCCCUGCUCCCUGGAGACUGGGAAAAGGCCGCAGGGCAGGGGGACUGGGCGGUGGUGGCUGGUGGUUUAAAGGUUGAACUUUCUCUGAAGCUCCUUUCCCCUUGCUCUUGGUCCCUGCCCCGCAAGCAAACCUGCCCCCUCUGCCUCCCAGUGCACCCAAUGACCCCCUCCCUUGGGGCGACUCCUGAUGAAGCACAACUCCCCGCAGGGCCCCCAGCCCACAGGGGUGGCCAUAUUUGGGCAGUUCCCAGUCCUGUGGGCUCGGCUAUCUGGGGAGCAGAUUUUGGGUCUGGAUCUCCCUGGGGAGUGGGUCCUGGGCUUGGAUCUUUCCCUAGGGGGCCCUCUUACUCCUUCCUCUCUCCUCCUCCUUCCCCAUUGCUGUAAAUAUUUCAACGAAAUGGAAAAGAAAAAAAAAAGACAAAAAAAAAAAAAAAGAAAAGAAAAAAAAUCUCAUCACUUGAAGCCACCGGGAGCCUGCGGCCCGGGCCAGCCCGGGCUUUCUCCGGAGCAGAGCAGCGCUGCUGGCCUGGCAGCCAGGACUUCUCCGUGUACGUGCAUCCCCAGUCCCCGCCGGGGCGGGCGGGCCGCCAGAGCAGCUUUUUACAAUCCAGAGACAGAAAACAAAAUCUAGAUGCAACAGCGAAACAAAGAACCCAUUUCCUUCCUGGCACCCUCCUUUCCUGCUCCGCCUGCCCGGCAUCAUCAGCCCUUCUGGGGCGUGUACCUCUCACUGCCUGCCCCAGGACCAGAGGCCUGUCUCCCCCUUCCCUCCCCACCGGCCCGGGGGAGACCUCUUCACACCCAAAGAUGCUUUGUCAAGAUGGCUGCGCUGUCCCUUUGAGUUCCUGCUUCUUGUAUAUUGCUCUGGGGACUCUCGCCGGGGAAGAUGGGGCUGAUUUCCCACCUAGAGAGGUUGAUGGCAGAAGGAAAAUGGGGAGGCACUGGGGUUGUGGAGGGCAUGGGUAUGGCUGAGGAGGGUGCUGGGAACGGCAAGGCGGUCUGGGGGAUGGGGAGGGGCAAAGGUGAGAGAUCACCUUCCCUAUCCUCCACCUUCCCGCAGGGAAGACGAAGCCAGGUGCCAGGGCUGGGGUCGGGACACCCAUGUUCUGGGCGGCUUGACCCCAAAUCCCAGACCCCGGAAGCUCCAGGCUCGGGAUGUGUCCUGAGCACCUGUCCCGGCCCCCUCCUCUCCAGCCUGUCAGGCCAGCCUCCCCAGCCCCCUUCCCUCAACUCUAGGGGCAGCAUAGCCCCAGGCCACCCUAGCCCAGCCCCUGCAUUGCCGUUUCCCCAGAGGUGGCCCCUCCACCUCUGCUCUGACCUCUCCCCAUCUCUCUGCCCCUCCUUUUCUCACAAGUGCCAUGAGUUUUCAAACAUCUUCGGGUCUCAGCCUGCUGCUGCCAUGAACUUUGUUGGGUUAAGGGGGAGGGGCUCUAGGAAGGAACUGGGGGGAAGGGGACAGGUAGGUGGCUGGAGGGACCCUUUUUGCUGCUAGAAAGCCCCUCCCUUCUCCCGGGGAGCUGGGGCUGGCUUGUCCCCAUCAAUUAGGGGAGAAGGGGUCAGACCAAAGAUGGUGGUUUGUCCCGUGUAAGGGAACAGGUGUGGGGAAGAGGUGGGGUUGGGUUCCAACUCUGGCUUUUUCUGGUAGAAAGGCCUAACCCAUUACACCAGAAGACCAUGGGUGAAGUCUAGAUGGGGAGGAGAAGUGAGGCCAGGGACAGUCUUGCCAGACGACUCUGAGGAGGGCAAGGGACAGUUCCAUGGCCCUUCCCGGACUGCACUAGGCUGGGAGCUCUGUUGUGUGGAGGGGUGGUCAGAGGUCUGUGAAGAGCGGGCAGGAGGCAUGAGCAGGCGAGGAGCUGGCCUGUCCCGGGAAGCAGCCCAGCCUGUGGCUGCCCCCGACACCAGGAGGAGGGCCAGGAGAGUUCCAGGGGGCUGAGGCACACAGAGAGGCCAACUUCCUCCCUGCCCAGCCUUCCUUGUAUCUCUCCAGACUCGGACAAUCAAAGGGAGAGAGGGUGUAUCGGGUCCUGUUCCAGCCGGCAUCGCCGGGUGGCUUCCAGGCCUCAGAGCUGUGUGGCAGGGCCCCCUGCUGGGGCUGGACAUCACUGCAGUCCAGUGCAAAGCCGCCCCCAGAGCCCAGGUGUCCCCCCAACCUAACCAGACCUGGUGCCUUGACGCCCCCACCCCAGCUGGGACGGUACAGAGAAGGGUCUUGGUUUCCUCUCCUACUCCCUUCCUUAGGCUCCUGAACUCGUUUGCUCCUAAAUCUUGUUAAUUCUUUUUCUCUGGAUUUUGGUUUCUUUUGGCUUUCCCUUGCCUUCCCCUUUCUCUGUCUCCAACACUCUUUCCCCAUGUCUUUCUGGCUGUCUCUAUGUUCCUCUUCUCUUAUCCUCAACUUUCUGUCCAUUCGGGCCUCCUCCCCACCUCCCACGCCCCAGCCCCUCCCUCCUUGGUCUCCUUUUCGAUAUGCCAAACCAAUUUUGGGUCGAGUGCAUUUAACGAGAACAAAACAAAAGGCUCAUAACAACAAGAACGUUUCAGAAAAAAACAAAAAGUUUUAAAAAAAUUGUUGAGUCAAAAAGUCAAACAAUAAAGAAAUUAAGAUUUCUUGGAA